GUUGCGCGCUGCAGGGCAACACCCCGGCGUCCCUGGAAGCUGGGGGAGCGGGUGGGUGUUGGGUGGCGUUGGGGGAGCUGCGCCUCGCCCAGAGCCUCGCCCGGAGCCUCGCCCGGAGCCUUCCGGGGUGGGGGAUAGUUGAGGACCUCAUCGAGGGAGGGGUUGGGCGGCGGGGAAGGGAGCGAGCGUGGCGGGGGACCCGAGGCACGCUCUCGAGCCAACGAGCGUGAUGCGCUCGAGUGUGGGCGGGGACUGAGGGAAGAAGUGAAAAUCGGACUGCCAGGCGACAGUUCCUCCGUUUGAAAUCUCGCCGGCUCCUGAGCGGGCCACCGGGCCCGGGCUGGGGGUCUGGCGGGAGAAAUAACUUUAUUUGGACUGAGAGCUGGAGAAUGAGAAUAGGACCUGAGAGUAUAUUGGGCUAAGGAGGAGAGGUGUUUGAGCCCAGAUGAGUCAUGGCUGGACGACCCCUCCGCAUAGGAGAUCAGCUGGUUCUGGAAGAAGAUUAUGAUGAGACCUACAUUCCUAGUGAGCAAGAAAUUCUUGAAUUUGCCCGGGAGAUUGGUAUUGAUCCCAUCAAGGAACCAGAACUGAUGUGGCUGGCGCGAGAGGGCAUCGUGGCCCCACUGCCUGGAGAGUGGAAACCAUGCCAGGACAUCACAGGUGACAUUUACUAUUUCAACUUCGCCAACGGGCAGUCUAUGUGGGACCAUCCAUGUGACGAACACUAUCGGAGCUUGGUGAUCCAAGAGCGGGCAAAGCUGUCAACUUCUGGGGCCAUUAAGAAGAAGAAAAAAAAAAAGGAAAAGAAAGACAAGAAGGACAGAGACCCCCCCAAAAGUUCGCUGGAAACGCAGCCUGAGGAGGGACUUCUGCCUCCUUCAUCCUUUCUCUGCAGCUUGUCUCCUCCGUCAGCACCUGGGCUUGCUGAUCUGGACCUAGAUCAAGAGAUGCAGGCUAUAAGUGAGGGAUCCUAUAACAAAGGAAAGAGCCCAGGCAUGCUGGGUGACACUCCCUGGCGUUUCAUGGGUGCCCUUCCCAGAAAGCUGCAGCCACUCUCCAAAGGCCAACCUUCCCAAAUCCACCAGGUCUUUGCUGACAUGGAGAAAAUCUUAGGCAGGGCCCCAGCCCAAUGCAGGAGAGAAUUAGGUGAUCAGCAGGGUCUGGAGAAACUCCAGAAGGCGACAGAGAAAAUCUACCUGGGGUUUUCAGAUCCUGAAACAGAAGAGCUGGAAAUGAGAAGCAGGCAGCAGAAACUGGGCACUCCAGCCCCUCAGAACACUGGGCUUCUCCAAAAUAUGCAGGAUGUGGUAGAAAGCAGGAACCAGGCCUCUGUCCACUCAAAGCUUUCUGAAGCCAUCAAAGGCCUGCCACUGAAAGGGGAGCAGCACAGCCACAGCUUAGCCAAACUGAGCCCCACUGGCCCUGGAGGGGACAAGGGCCAAAGCCCCAUUCCCAUGUCAUCCCCUGAGGAGGAGCCCUCCCUGUCCUCUUGUUCUUCCGGCCACAUGUUGCCUGCCAGGAAGAGCAAGUUGUUGUUAGAUAGCAGCCCUACUGAAGACCUGAGCUGGCAGGGAGUUCCUGGGGAAGGUGGGAGCAUAGGCAGCGGGAGGAGGAGGAGAGAACCUCCUGGACUGUGGAUGGAACAGGUCUCCAAGCUUGUCAAUAAGGAUAUCCCAGGAAGCUGCAAGGAAACAGAGCCCAGUGACCCUGAGGCUCUAGGGGCCUCAGCUGAAGAUCUACCUCAGGGUCUCUUGCUAAUACCACCUGAAACCCUGGCAUCAGAACCAGCUCAGAAUCCCCUUUUAGGGAGGGCUCCCGAGGAGCCUCCUGCCAGUGAGAAGAGACAGGCCCUAGGGUCUGCAGAGCUCCCUUAUAAAGAUCAGAAGCCUAGCUUGUCUGGGCCUGACUUGGAGAGCAGCAGCAGCAGCAGCAGCAACAGCAACCUGGCCUCACACCUGGGCUCUCCUGUCCUGGAUGAGGUGAACAACUUCCCUUGGAACCUGCAGAGCUCACGGGGAUCUGAGGAGGGUAUGGCUCAGUCAGACUCGGGUCUCAGAGAUCAACACUUCAGCCCCUUCUUAGAUCCUCACAUGUCCCACAUGCAGAGCCCUGACGAGGAGCAGUCAGAAAGUGAAGACUACUCUGAGGACCAGAGGUUCUACCAGCACAUCCUGCAGAUGGUCAAGAUCUCCAGGUGGCCGGAGGGCCUGGGGCUGCCUGAGAGCAUGCAGGACAUGCCGUGCAGACACAGCGCCAGCACAGUCUGUUGCAUGGCAGCUGAGUCUUCUAGGAUGUCUAGUGAGGGUGAGCACGAGGCCAUCAGAGUCAUGGAGAGGGACUCGAGGUUUCUGUCAUGGGAGCCAGAGCUGCUGGAACAUCCUCAGGAGGUGGCCCUCGCCCCUGCUUGGCAAGAGGCCUCUCAGCAAGCCCAUUUCCAGCCAAGCAGCAGCACCCUCAGGCAGGGGCUAGUCCAGCAGAGCUCCAGCAGAGGGCUUACUACAGAGCCAGGCAAGAUGCAGCAUCUCAACCAGGCCUUGGGUUCCUCAUUAGCCCCAGUUCAUGUUCCUCUUGGGGGCCUGGCUCCUUUACGAGGUCUUGUGGAUACCCCACCCUCUGCUCUUCGUGGAUCUCAAAGCGUGAGCCUGGGGAGCUCAGUGGAGUCUGGACGUCAGCUUGGAGAACUCAUGCUGCCUUCACAGGGUCUCAAGACCUCUGCUUAUACAAAGGGUCUCUUGGGCUCCAUAUAUGAGGACAAGACUGCUCUCAGCCUCUUGGGUUUAGGAGAAGAAACCAAUGAGGAGGAUGAGGAGGAAAGUGACAACCAGAGUGUCCACAGCUCAAGUGAGCCUCUUAGGAACCUACACCUGGACAUUGGGGCACUGGGGGGUGACUUUGAGUAUGAGGAGUCUCUGAGAACAAGCCAGCCAGAGGAGAAGAAGGAUGUUUCUCUGGAUUCAGAUGCUGCCGGUCCCCCUACUCCCUGCAAGCCCUCCAGCCCAGGUGCAGACAGCAGUCUGAGCAGUGCUGUUGGCAAAGGGCGACAGGGAAGUGGAGCAAGACCUGGUCUUCCAGAAAAAGAGGAAAAUGAGAAGAGUGAACCUAAGAUUUGCAGGAAUCUGGUGACCCCCAAGGCAGACCCUACAGGCAGUGAGCCUGCCAAAGCCUCUGAAAAGGAAGCACCAGAGGACACAGUAGAUGCAGGAGAGGAGGGUUCCAGGAGGGAAGAGGCAGCCAAGGAGCCAAAGAAGAAGGCUUCUGCUCUGGAAGAGGGCAGUUCAGACGCCAGCCAAGAACUGGAAAUUAGUGAACACAUGAAGGAACCACAGCUCUCAGACUCCAUAGCUUCUGACCCCAAGUCCUUCCAUGGCCUGGACUUCGGUUUUCGCAGCCGGAUCUCGGAGCACCUGCUGGAUGUUGAUGUGCUUUCCCCAGUCCUGGGUGGAGCUUGUCGGCAGGCCCAGCAACCACUGGGAAUAGAAGACAAGGAUGACAGCCAGUCCAGCCAAGAUGAGCUGCAGAGCAAGCAGUCCAAAGGCCUGGAGGAGAGUUCUCUUCCCGCUCUCCAAAUGGAGGGGCCUGACUCUGCUGCUCUGCCCGGCCUGACCAGGUUAUCUCCUCCACUUCCACACGAGGAGCGGGCCCAGAGUCCCCCUCGCAGCCUGGCCACUGAAGAAGAGCCUCCCCAGGGCCCCGAGGGGCAGCCCGAGUGGAAGGAGGCAGAGGAGCUUGGGGAGGACUCUGCAGCCAGCCUCAGCCUGCAGCUGUCCCUCCAGAGGGAGCAGGCCCCAAGCCCACCUGCUGCCUGUGAGAAGGGCAAGGAGCAGCAUUCCCAGGCCGAGGAGCUGGGCCCUGGGCAGGAAGAGGCAGAGGAUCCUGAGGAGAAGGUGGCGGUCAGCCCCACCCCGCCAGUCUCUCCAGAGGUGCGAUCCACAGAGCCUGUGGCUCCCCCAGAGCAGCUCUCAGAGGCUGCACUAAAGGCCAUGGAAGAGGCAGUGGCCCAAGUACUCGAGCAAGACCAGAGGCACCUGCUGGAAUCCAAGCAAGAGAAGAUGCAGCAACUGCGGGAGAAGCUGUGCCAAGAGGAGGAAGAGGAGAUCCUCCGGCUUCACCAGCAGAAAGAGCAAUCUCUCAGUUCCUUGAGGGAGCGGCUGCAGAAAGCCAUUGAGGAGGAGGAGGCCCGGAUGAGAGAGGAGGAAAGCCAGAGGCUAUCCUGGCUCCGAGCUCAGGUCCAGUCCAGCACACAAGCAGAUGAGGACCAAAUCAGGGCUGAGCAAGAGGCUUCCCUGCAGAAACUGAGAGAAGAGUUGGAGUCUCAACAGAAGGCUGAGAGGGCCAGCUUGGAACAGAAAAAUAGGCAAAUGCUGGAGCAGCUCAAGGAAGAGAUAGAGGCUUCGGAGAAGAGCGAGCAGGCUGCCCUGAAUGCUGCAAAGGAGAAGGCUCUGCAGCAGCUGAGGGAGCAGCUGGAAGGGGAGAGGAAAGAAGCUGUGGCAACGCUGGAGAAGGAGCACAGUGCUGAGCUGGAGCGGCUCUGCUCCUCAUUGGAGGCCAAGCACCGGGAGGUGGUCUCCAGCCUCCAGAAGAAGAUACAGGAAGCUCAACAGAAAGAGGAGGCCCAGCUGCAGAAGUGCCUUGGGCAAGUGGAGCACAGAGUUCACCAGAAGUCUUAUCACGUGGCUGGGUAUGAGCACGAGCUCAGCAGUCUCCUGCGAGAGAAGCGCCAGGAAGUGGAAGGGGAGCAUGAGAGGAGGUUGGACAAGAUGAAGGAGGAGCACCAGCAAGUGAUGGCUAAGGCCAGAGAGCAGUAUGAAGCUGAGGAGAGGAAGCAGCGGGCUGAGCUUCUGGGGCACCUGACCGGAGAGCUGGAGCGCCUGCAGAGGGCCCAUGAACGAGAACUGGAGACUGUGAGGCAGGAGCAACACAAGCGUCUUGAGGACUUGCGGCGCCGGCACAGGGAGCAGGAAAGGAAGCUCCAGGAUUUAGAGUUGGACCUUGAAACCAGAGCUAAAGAUGUCAAGGCCAGAUUGGCUCUGCUGGAGGUCCAGGAGGAGACCGCCCGGAGGGAGAAGCAGCAGCUGCUUGAUGUGCAGAGGCAGGUUGCUCUGAAGAGUGAGGAAGCCACAGCCACCCAUCAGCAGCUGGAGGAGGCACAGAAGGAGCACACCCACCUGUUGCAGUCAAACCAGCAGCUCCGAGAAAUUCUUGAUGAGCUGCAGGCCCGCAAGCUGAAGCUGGAGUCCCAAGUGGAUCUGCUGCAGGCUCAGAGCCAGCAACUGCAGAAACACUUCAGCAGCCUGGAGGCUGAAGCUCAAAAGAAGCAGCACCUGUUGAGAGAAGUGACAGUUGAGGAAAAUAAUGCUUCCCCACAUUUUGAGCCAGAUCUCCAUAUUGAGGACCUGAGGAAAUCCCUUGGAACAAACCAGACCAAAGAGGUGUCUUCUUCUCUCUCCCAGAGCAAGGAGGACUUAUACUUGGACAGCCUGUCCUCCCACAAUGUCUGGCACCUCCUCUCUGCUGAGGGGGUAGCCCUCCGUAGUGCCAAGGAGUUCCUUGUGCAGCAGACACGCUCCAUGCGGAGGCGGCAGACAGCUCUGAAAGCUGCCCAGCAGCAUUGGCGCCAUGAGCUGGCCAGUGCGCAGGAGGUGGCCAAAGACCCACCAGGCAUCAAGGCCCUGGAAGAUAUGCGCAAGAACCUGGAGAAGGAGACCAGGCACCUGGAUGAGAUGAAGUCGGCCAUGCGGAAAGGCCACAACCUGCUGAAGAAGAAAGAGGAGAAGCUGAAUCAGUUGGAGUCCUCUCUUUGGGAAGAGGCCUCAGAUGAGGGCACUCUGGGAGGAUCCCCCACCAAGAAGGCAGUAACCUUCGACCUCAGUGACAUGGACAGCCUGAGCAGUGAAAGUUCUGAAUCUUUUUCCCCGCCUCACCGUGAGUGGUGGCGGCAGCAGAGGAUCGACUCAACCCCGAGUCUCACCUCCCGCAAGAUCCACGGGCUUAGCCACUCCCUCCGGCAGAUCAGCAGCCAGCUGAGCAGUGUCCUCAGCAUCCUGGACAGCCUCAACCCUCAGUCGCCGCCGCCGCUCCUCGCCUCCAUGCCAGCCCAGCUCCCUCCCCGGGACCCUAAGAGCACCCCCACCCCCACCUACUAUGGCUCCCUGGCCAGGUUCUCAGCCUUAUCAUCUGCUACACCCACGUCCACCCAAUGGGCCUGGGAUUCAGGGCAGGGGCCCAGGCUCCCCUCCUCUGUGGCUCAAACGGUGGACGACUUCCUGUUGGAGAAGUGGCGCAAGUAUUUUCCAUCUGGCAUCCCGCUGCUCAGCAACAGCCCCACCCCGCUGGAGAGCAGGCUGGGUUACAUGUCUGCCAGUGAGCAGCUCCGGCUCCUACAGCACUCCCAUUCGCAAGUCCCUGAGGCGGGCAGCACCACCUUUCAGGGCAUAAUUGAGGCCAACCGGAGGUGGCUGGAACGUGUCAAGAAUGACCCCAGGUUACCUCUCUUCUCGUCAACACCCAAGCCAAAAGCUACUUUGAGCCUCCUGCAGCUGGGCCUUGAUGAGCACAACAGAGUGAAGGUGUAUCGCUUCUGAGGCCCUGAGCAGGGGCUUGGGGCAGCCCAGCCUCUCCUCCACCCAGACCAAGUGCCUGAGGAGCUGCCUGCCUUCUUCCAUCUGAGAAAGCACCCUCCUUCCCCCUUUGACUUGCAGGAGCCACCAGGGACCAGGGGGUUGAGUGGAACAGUAAAGCCACACAUUCUGUGACUAUAUAACCUAUCUCAGGCUAAAAUGUGUGGACUCGUACGAGCUCUUGUCAUUGACAUGGCAAGCUGAUGGCGUGCGGUGGCUGCGGGGUAUCAGGGCCGGGAGCCCUUUGGGAGGAAGGGAGGCGUUAGAGGAGCUGCCUUCGGAGGCUCAGGGAGUCCCUUUGGAGCUGGUUGUUUCCUUGGCCCUGCAGCGCACUGCUCGGGGCUCCCAAGGAGGUUGUGUGUAUGGUUCUUAAUUCAUCAGGACAAAGACCCCCAGCAUGUGUGUACCCUGGGACCCGAUUUCUCUGGGCCCACAUCUAUCUCCAAUACCUCAGCCUCAGAUCAGACCCUUUCUUUUUUGUCUUUCUUCUCUUAAUUUUUAAAUGCCUCUUUUCUUGAGCAUUCCAUCUCUCUUUUUGACCCUCUCAGGACUGGGCUUAGCUGUCCAGAGCCCUGCCGGAGGGUGCUGGGGGCUGUCCCUCUGCAGGCACUGUGUUUUCCUCAGGGGCUGUCCUCAGAACACCCCUCCUGCUCCCUGGGGCUCCUCAGGGAGCCAUUUCAGCUGGAGUCUCAGGUCUCAAAAACAACUUCUCCAGGAGGCCAAAAAAAGACUGGGUUGGCUUCUGGUCCUCAUGAUGGCUUUUAUCCUCCUGGGACACUUUGGGUAUAUUCAUGGGCAUUGUUUCCAUCUGUCUUUUCUACCUGUGCCACCCCUGCCCUGAUUCCACGGCUGCCUCAGGCAGGCAGGCAAGGAGCUAGGCCGGUGCCCGGCCCUGGCAGCAAGGGGUCUUUGUGCAGUUGGAGAUGCUGCCGUUGUGGCAGAGCGUCCUGCAGCCCCGCUUCCAUCAGCAGGCUCUGGGGUGGGGGCUUUGCAGGGGAUGCUCUCUGAUGUUUGUUCCGUUGUUUAAAUAAAAUGCACUUAUUUUUGUUUUUUUUUUUGCAA